GUUCCAGAACUGAGGGAUUCUUCAAAACUUCAUGAUUCUCUCUAUAAUGAGGAUUGUACUUUCCAACAGCUUGGAACUUACAUUGAUUCUAUCAGAGAUCCUGUCCAUAACAGAGUCACCCUAGAACUGAGUAAUGGCUCCAUGGUUAGGAUCACUGUUCCUGAAAUUGCCACCUCUGAGUUAGUACAAACAUGUUUGCAAACAAUUAAGUUUAUCCUGCCAAAAGAAAUAGCAGUUCAGAUGCUUGUCAAGUGGUACAAUGUCCACAGUGCUCCAGUAGGACCCAGUUAUCACUCAGAGUGGAAUUUAUUUGUGACUUGUCUCAUGAACGUGAUGGGUUUUAACACAGACCGCUUAGCAUGGACUAGAAAUUUUGACUUUGAAGGAUCACUUUCCCCUGUCAUUGCACCCAAAAAAGCAAGGCCUUCUGAGACUGGAUCUGAUGAUAAGUUGAGAGGAUUCUAUUUUGCAAAGCUGUAUUAUGAAGCUAAAGAAUAUGAUCUUGCUAAAAAAUACGUAUGUACUUACCUUAGUGUGCAAGAGAGGGAUCCCAGAGCUCACAGAUUUCUGGGUCUUCUUUAUGAAUUGGAAGAAAACACAGAGAAAGCCGUUGAAUGUUACAGGCGUUCACUGGAAUUAAACCCACCACAAAAAGAUCUUGUGUUGAAGAUUGCAGAAUUGCUUUGUAAAAAUGAUGUUACUGAUGGAAGAGCAAAAUACUGGGUUGAAAGGGCAGCGAAACUUUUCCCAGGAAGUCCUGCAAUUUAUAAACUAAAGGAACAUCUUCUAGAUUGUGAAGGUGAAGAUGGAUGGAAUAAACUUUUUGACUGGAUUCAGUCAGAACUUUAUGUAAGACCUGAUGACGUCCAUAUGAACAUCCGGCUAGUGGAGUUGUAUCGCUCAAAUAAAAGAUUGAAGGAUGCUGUGGCCCGCUGCCAUGAGGCAGAGAGGAACAUAGCUUUGCGUUCAAGUUUAGAGUGGAAUUCGUGUGUUGUACAGACCCUUAAGGAAUAUCUGGAGUCUUUACAGUGUUUGGAGUCUGAUAAAAGUGACUGGCGAGCAACCAAUACAGACUUACUGCUGGCCUAUGCUAAUCUUAUGCUUCUUACGCUUUCCACUAGAGAUGUGCAGGAAAGUAGAGAAUUACUGGAAAGUUUUGAUAGUGCUCUUCAGUCUGCAAAAUCUUCUUUGGGUGGAAAUGAUGAACUGUCAGCUACUUUCUUAGAAAUGAAAGGACAUUUCUACAUGCAUGCUGGUUCUCUGCUCUUGAAGAUGGGUCAGCAUGGUAAUAAUGUUCAAUGGCAAGCUCUUUCUGAGCUGGCUGCAUUGUGCUAUGUCAUAGCAUUUCAGGUUCCAAGACCAAAGAUUAAAUUAAUAAAAGGUGAAGCUGGACAAAAUCUGCUGGAAAUGAUGGCCUGUGACCGACUGAGCCAAUCAGGGCAUAUGUUGCUAAACUUAAGUCGUGGCAAGCAAGAUUUUUUAAAAGAGGUUGUUGAAACUUUUGCCAACAAAAGCGGGCAGUCUGUGUUAUAUAAUGCUCUGUUUUCUAGUCAGUCAUCUAAGGAUACAUCUUUUCUUGGUAGCGAUGAUAUUGGAAACAUUGAUGUACAAGAACCAGAGCUUGAAGAUUUGGCUAGAUACGAUGUUGGUGCUAUUCAAGCACAUAAUGGUAGUCUUCAGCACCUUACUUGGCUUGGCUUACAGUGGAAUUCAUUGCCUGCUUUACCUGGAAUCCGAAAAUGGCUAAAACAGCUUUUCCAUCAUUUGCCCCAGGAAACCUCAAGGCUUGAAACAAAUGCACCUGAAUCAAUAUGUAUUUUAGAUCUUGAAGUAUUUCUCCUUGGAGUAGUAUAUACCAGCCACUUACAAUUAAAGGAGAAAUGUAAUUCUCACCACAGCUCCUAUCAGCCGUUAUGCCUGCCCCUUCCUGUGUGUAAACGGCUUUGUACAGAGAGACAAAAAUCUUGGUGGGAUGCGGUUUGUACUCUGAUUCACAGAAAAGCAGUACCUGGAAACUCAGCAGAAUUGAGACUUGUAGUUCAGCAUGAAAUAAACACUCUAAGAGCCCAGGAAAAACAUGGCCUUCAACCUGCUCUGCUUGUACAUUGGGCAAAAUGCCUUCAGAAAAUGGGCAGGGGUCUUAAUUCUUCUUAUGAUCAACAAGAAUACAUAGGGAGAAGUGUUCAUUAUUGGAAGAAAGUUUUGCCAUUGUUGAAGAUAAUAAAGAAGAACAGUAUUCCUGAACCUAUUGAUCCUCUGUUUAAACAUUUUCAUAGUGUAGACAUUCAGGCAUCAGAAAUUGUUGAGUAUGAAGAAGAUGCACACAUAACUUUUGCUAUAUUGGAUGCAGUACAUGGAAAUAUAGAAGAUGCUGUGACUGCUUUUGAAUCUAUAAAAAGUGUUGUUUCUUAUUGGAAUCUUGCACUGAUUUUUCACAGGAAAGCAGAAGACAUUGAAAAUGAUGCCGUUUUUCCUGAAGAACAAGAAGAAUGCAAAAAUUAUCUGAGAAAGACCAGGGACUACCUAAUAAAGAUUAUAGAUGACAGUGAUUCAAAUCUUUCAGUGGUCAAGAAAUUGCCUGUGCCCCUGGAGUCUGUAAAAGAGAUGCUUAAGUCAGUCAUGCAGGAACUCGAAGACUAUAGUGAAGGAGGUCCUCUCUAUAAAAAUGGUUCUUUGCGAAAUGCAGAUUCAGAAAUAAAACAUUCUACACCAUCUCCUACCAAAUAUUCACUAUCACCAAGUAAAAGUUACAAGUAUUCUCCCAAAACACCACCUCGAUGGGCAGAAGAUCAGAAUUCUUUACGGAAAAUGAUUUGCCAAGAAGUAAAGGCCAUUACGAAACUAAAUAGCAGUAAGUCAGCAUCCCGUCAUCGUUGGCCCACAGAGAAUUAUGGACCAGACUCGGUGCCUGAUGGAUAUCAGGGGUCACAGACAUUUCAUGGGGCUCCACUAACAGUUGCAACUACUGGCCCUUCAGUAUAUUAUAGUCAGUCACCAGCAUAUAAUUCCCAGUAUCUUCUCAGACCAGCAGCUAAUGUUACUCCCACAAAGGGUUCUUCUAAUACAGAAUUUAAGUCAACCAAAGAAGGAUUUUCCAUCGCUGUGUCUGCUGAUGGAUUUAAAUUUGGCAUUUCGGAACCAGGAAAUCAAGAAAAGAAAAGUGAAAAGCCUCUUGAAAAUGAUACUGGCUUCCAGGCUCAGGAUAUUAGUGGCCAGAAGAAUGGCCGUGGUGUGAUUUUUGGCCAAACAAGUAGCACUUUUACAUUUGCAGAUGUUGCAAAAUCAACUUCAGGAGAAGGAUUUCAGUUUGGCAAAAAAGACCCCAAUUUCAAGGGAUUUUCAGGUGCUGGAGAAAAAUUAUUCUCAUCACAAUGCGGUAAAAUGGCCAAUAAAGCAAACACUUCCGGUGACUUUGAGAAAGAUGAUGAUGCCUGUAAGACUGAGGACAGCGAUGACAUCCAUUUUGAACCAGUAGUUCAAAUGCCUGAAAAAGUAGAACUUGUAACAGGAGAAGAAGGUGAAAAAGUUCUGUAUUCACAGGGGGUAAAACUAUUUAGAUUUGAUGCUGAGAUAAGUCAGUGGAAAGAAAGGGGCUUGGGGAACUUAAAAAUUCUCAAAAAUGAGGUCAAUGGCAAACCAAGAAUGCUGAUGCGAAGAGACCAAGUACUAAAAGUGUGUGCUAAUCAUUGGAUAACAACUACAAUGAACCUGAAGCCCCUCUCUGGAUCAGAUAGAGCAUGGAUGUGGUUAGCCAGUGAUUUCUCUGAUGGUGAUGCCAAACUAGAGCGGUUGGCAGCACAAUUUAAAACACCAGAGCUGGCUGAAGAAUUCAAGCAGAAAUUUGAGGAAUGCCAGCGGCUUCUGUUAGACAUACCACUUCAAACUCCCCAUAAACUUGUAGAUACUGGCAGAGCUGCCAAGCUAAUACAGAGAGCUGAAGAAAUGAAGAGUGGACUGAAAGAUUUCAAAACGUUUUUGACAAAUGAUCAAACAAAAGUCACUGAGGAAGAAAAUAAGGGUUCAGGUACAGGUGCAGCCGGUGCCUCAGACACAACAAUAAAACCCAAUCCUGAAAACACUGGGCCCACAUUAGAAUGGGAUAACUAUGAUUUAAGGGAAGAUGCUUUGGAUGAUAAUGUUAGUAGUAGCUCAGUACAUGAUUCUCCGUUGGCAAGUAGCCCUGUGAGAAAAAAUAUUUUCCGCUUUGAUGAGUCAACAACAGGAUUUAACUUCAGUUUUAAAUCUGCUUUGAGUCUAUCUAAGUCUCCUGCCAAGUUGAAUCAGAGUGGGACUUCAGUUGGCACUGAUGAAGAAUCUGAUGUUACUCAAGAAGAAGAGAGAGAUGGACAGUACUUUGAACCUGUUGUUCCUUUACCUGAUCUAGUUGAAGUAUCCAGUGGUGAGGAAAAUGAACAAGUUGUUUUUAGUCACAUGGCAGAACUCUACAGAUAUGAUAAAGAUGUUGGUCAAUGGAAAGAAAGGGGCAUUGGUGAUAUAAAGAUUUUACAGAAUUAUGAUAAUAAGCAAGUUCGUAUAGUGAUGAGAAGGGACCAAGUAUUAAAACUUUGUGCCAAUCACAGAAUAACUCCAGACAUGAGUUUGCAAAAUAUGAAAGGGACAGAAAGAGUAUGGGUGUGGACUGCAUGUGAUUUUGCAGAUGGAGAAAGAAAAGUAGAGCAUUUAGCUGUUCGUUUUAAACUACAGGAUGUUGCAGACUCAUUUAAGAAAAUUUUUGAUGAAGCAAAAACAGCCCAGGAAAAAGAUUCUUUGAUAACACCUCAUGUUUCUCGGUCAAGCACUCCCAGAGAGUCACCAUGUGGCAAAAUUGCUGUAGCUGUAUUAGAAGAAACCACAAGAGAGAGGACAGAUGUUAUUCAGGGUGAUGAUGUAGCAGAUGCAGCUUCAGAAGUUGAAGUGUCUAGCACAUCUGAAACAACAACAAAAGCAGUGGUUUCUCCUCCAAAGUUUGUAUUUGGUUCAGAGUCUGUUAAAAGAAUUUUUAGUAGUGAAAAAUCAAACCCAUUUGCAUUUGGCAACAGUUCUGCCACUGGGUCUUUGUUUGGAUUUAGUUUUAAUGCACCUUUGAAAAGUAACGAUAGUGAAACUAGUUCAGUAGCCCAGAGUGGAUCUGAAAGCAAAGUGGAACCUAAAAAAUGUGAACUGUCAAAGAACUCUGAUAUCGAACAGUCUUCAGAUAGCAAAGUCAAAAAUCUCUCUGCUUCCUUUCCAAUGGAAGAAUCUUCAAUCAACUACACAUUUAAAACACCAGAAAAGGAGCCUCCAUUAUGGCAUGCUGAAUUUACCAAAGAAGAAUUGGUUCAGAAGCUCAGUUCCACCACAAAAAGUGCAGAUCAGUUAAACGGCCUGCUUCGGGAAACAGAGGCAACCAGUGCAGUCCUUAUGGAGCAAAUUAAGCUUCUCAAAAGUGAAAUAAGAAGAUUGGAAAGGAAUCAAGAGGAGUCUGCAGCUAACGUGGAACACUUGAAGAACGUCUUGCUGCAGUUCAUUUUCUUGAAGCCAGGUAGUGAGAGAGAGAGCCUUCUUCCUGUUAUAAAUACGAUGUUGCAGCUCAGCCCUGAAGAAAAGGGAAAACUUGCUGCGGUUGCUCAAGGUCUUCAAGAAACCUCCAUACCCAAGAAAAAAUAGAAAGCAACCAUGUUCUACUAUGGUGCCAAAAAUAGUUGAACAUCGACAUCAAAAAGAUUCUUUCUGUCUGCUUAUUCACAUAUUCUGGUUUGAAUUAAAAGUGAUGAAAUUAUCCUAAAUACAGUUGGCCCUCUGUAUCCAUGGGUUCCACAUCCACAAAUUCAACCAACUGUGGAUGGAAAAGACUUGAAAAAGAUGAGAGAAAAUAACAAUAUGACAAUAAAACAUAAUACAAAUAAAAACAAUACAGUAUAACAACGAUUACAUAGCAUUUACAUUAUAUUAGGGAUUGCACAAGAGAAGGUAUGUAGGUUAUAUGCAAAUACUGCACCAUUUUACAUAAGGGACUUGAGAAGCAUGGAUUUUGGUAGCCACAGGGGUCCUGGAACCAAUCCCUCACAGACACAGACGGACACUUUACAGUAGAUGAACACAAAGAUGAAAGGAAAAGUCUGACCUAGGUCUGCGGGGAGAAGUGGAACUCCAUUUUUGACAGGUGAUGCCAUUUUUUGUUUUGGACAUCGUCCCUCUGUAGUUCUUUCCAUUCCCAGUCUUGCACUCUGAAAGAUACACUGAAGGAAAGUCCACACAGUGGUCAAAGUCUUUCACAAGACACCACGUGAAGGUCUGCACAGCACAGUCACAUUGAGAAAAAGAUCUCAUGCACCAGACCCCCUGUUUCUGCUUUCUAAAAGAUCAUCUUUUGCACCUGCAAAAAGGCUGCAGUAAACUGGGCCAUUCCAUACUUUGAUUCAUGUAUUCAAAUGCUACUUAUGAGCUCUCUGUGUAUUGAGCCCCACCAGGAUGCUGGGGACACACGGGGCACAGUGCAGCCAGAGGCUUGGCCAUCAUAGAGCUCACAUUCUAGUGGAAUCAGACAGGGGGGUUACAGGAAAUAUUCAAGUAAACAAUAUAAAAUGAGAUCACUUAAUGAUGAUACAUGGAUACAUGUUACAUACAUGAUGAGACAGAGUAAGAGAAUGGGGAAAGGGUUUUUAGAUGGGGGAAUGGCAGGCUUUUCCGAGGCUGAAAGAGAUCCAACCCACUUCUAUUUCUUCAGGCUCCCAGUGAUAUGAAAAAGUGCCAAACAGGACUAUAAAAUUGUGGUCUACUGUAAAUGGUUUGCAGUAAAAGUUCUCAACCAGCUUCCACUCAACCAACUCACCAGUUAGACAAUGGGCCCUCUCCUGUGUUUAAAACAGUCCGGUGCCCACCUGGGUCCACAUGCAGCUGGCAGGUGUUUGCUAGUGUGCCCACCCAUGUCUGUUCCCCCCACGUGAGUUAUGUGCUUACAACGAGUCGUUUCUUUGCAUUUUCCAACUUUCUUACAUUUAUAUUUAAUUAAAGAUGAUCUAAACUGAGAAAUGAAUGUGAAAAGAAACAAAGCUCUUUUUUGUUUGGUUUUUAACUAAAUUAAAUGUUUUUAACAAGU